GCCUGCUCUCCGGCGGAGCUGCGUGAGGCCCGGCCGGCCCCGGCCCCCCCCUUCCGGCCGCCCCCGCCUCCUGGCCCACGCCUGCCCGCGCUCUGCCCACCAGCGCCUCCAUCGGGCAAGGCGGCCCCGCGUCGACGCCGCCCGCUGCCUCGCUGCUGACUCCCGUCCCGGGCGCCGUCCGCGGGGUCGCGCUCCGCCGGGCCUGCGGAUUCCCCGCCGCCUCCUCUUCAUCUACCUCAACUCCCCCCAUCCCCGCUUCGCCCGAGGAGGCGGUUCCCCCCGCAGGCAGUCCGGCUCGCAGGCCGCCGGCGUUGUCACCCCCCCCCGCGCUCCCCCUCCAGCCCUCCCCCCGGCGCGCAGCCUCGGGCCGCUCCCCUUUCCGCGCUGCGUCCCGGAGCGGCCCCGGUGCCGCCACCGCCUGUCCCCCUCCCGAGGCCCGGGCUCGCGACGGCAGAGGGCUCCGUCGGCCCAAACCGAGCUGGGCGCCCGCGGUCCGGGUGCAGCCUCCACUCCGCCCCCCAGUCACCGCCUCCCCCGGCCCCUCGACGUGGCGCCCUUCCCUCCGCUUCUCUGUGCUCCCCGCGCCCCUCUUGGCGUCUGGCCCCGGCCCCCGCUCUUUCUCCCGCAACCUUCCCUUCGCUCCCUCCCGUCCCCCCCAGCUCCUAGCCUCCGACUCCCUCCCCCCCUCACGCCCGCCCUCUCGCCUUCGCCGAACCAAAGUGGAUUAAUUACACGCUUUCUGUUUCUCUCCGUGCUGUUCUCUCCCGCUGUGCGCCUGCCCGCCUCUCGCUGUCCUCUCUCCCCCUCGCCCUCUCUUCGGCCCCCCCCUUUCACGUUCACUCUGUCUCUCCCACUAUCUCUGCCCCCCUCUAUCCUUGAUACAACAGCUGACCUCAUUUCCCGAUACCUUUUCCCCCCCGAAAAGUACAACAUCUGGCCCGCCCCAGCCCGAAGACAGCCCGUCCUCCCUGGACAAUCAGACGAAUUCUCCCCCCCCCCCCAAAAAAAAGCCAUCCCCCCGCUCUGCCCCGUCGCACAUUCGGCCCCCGCGACUCGGCCAGAGCGGCGCUGGCAGAGGAGUGUCCGGCAGGAGGGCCAACGCCCGCUGUUCGGUUUGCGACACGCAGCAGGGAGGUGGGCGGCAGCGUCGCCGGCUUCCAGACACCAAUGGGAAUCCCAAUGGGGAAGUCGAUGCUGGUGCUUCUCACCUUCUUGGCCUUCGCCUCGUGCUGCAUUGCUGCUUACCGCCCCAGUGAGACCCUGUGCGGCGGGGAGCUGGUGGACACCCUCCAGUUCGUCUGUGGGGACCGCGGCUUCUACUUCAGCAGGCCCGCAAGCCGUGUGAGCCGUCGCAGCCGUGGCAUCGUUGAGGAGUGCUGUUUCCGCAGCUGUGACCUGGCCCUCCUGGAGACGUACUGUGCUACCCCCGCCAAGUCCGAGAGGGACGUGUCGACCCCUCCGACCGUGCUUCCGGACAACUUCCCCAGAUACCCCGUGGGCAAGUUCUUCCAAUAUGACACCUGGAAGCAGUCCACCCAGCGCCUGCGCAGGGGCCUGCCUGCCCUCCUGCGUGCCCGCCGGGGUCACGUGCUCGCCAAGGAGCUCGAGGCGUUCAGGGAGGCCAAACGUCACCGUCCCCUGAUUGCUCUACCCACCCAAGACCCCGCCCACGGGGGCGCCCCCCCAGAGAUGGCCAGCAAUCGGAAGUGAGCAAAACUGCCGCAAGUCUGCAGCCCGGCGCCACCAUCCUGCAGCCUCCUCCUGACCACGGACGUUUCCAUCAGGUUCCAUCCCGAAAAUCUCUCGGUUCCACGUCCCCCUGGGGCUUCUCCUGACCCAGUCCCCGUGCCCCGCCUCCCCGAAACAGGCUACUCUCCUCGGCCCCCUCCAUCGGGCUGAGGAAGCACAGCAGCAUCUUCAAACAUGUACAAAAUCGAUUGGCUUUAAACACCCUUCACAUACCCUCCCCCCAAAUUAUCCCCAAUUAUCCCCACACAUAAAAAAUCAAAACAUUAAACUAACCCCCUUCCCCCCCCCCCACAACAACCCUCUUAAAACUAAUUGGCUUUUUAGAAACACCCCACAAAAGCUCAGAAAUUGGCUUUAAAAAAAACAACCACCAAAAAAAAUCAAUUGGCUAAAAAAAAAAAGUAUUAAAAACGAAUUGGCUGAGAAACAAUUGGCAAAAUAAAGGAAUUUGGCACUCCCCACCCCCCUCUUUCUCUUCUCCCUUGGACUUUGAGUCAAAUUGGCCUGGACUUGAGUCCCUGAACCAGCAAAGAGAAAAGAAGGACCCCAGAAAUCACAGGUGGGCACGUCGCUGCUACCGCCAUCUCCCUUCUCACGGGAAUUUUCAGGGUAAACUGGCCAUCCGAAAAUAGCAACAACCCAGACUGGCUCCUCACUCCCUUUUCCAUCACUAAAAAUCACAGAGCAGUCAGAGGGACCCAGUAAGACCAAAGGAGGGGAGGACAGAGCAUGAAAACCAAAAUCCAUGCAAAUGAAAUGUAAUUGGCACGACCCUCACCCCCAAAUCUUACAUCUCAAUUCCCAUCCUAAAAAGCACUCAUACUUUAUGCAUCCCCGCAGCUACACACACACAACACACAGCACACGCAUGAACACAGCACACACACGAGCACAGCACACACACAAACGCACAGCACACACAGCACACAGAUGAGCACACAGCACACACACAAACGCACAGCACACACACGCACACACAUGCACACACAGCACACAAACGCACGGCACACACACGCACACACAUGCACACACAGCACACACACAAACGCACAGCACACACAAACGCACAGCACACACGCACACACAGCACACACACGAGCACACAGCACACAAACGCACAGCACACGCACACACAUGCACACACAGCACACACACUAGCACACAGCACACACACAAAGACACAGCACACACAUGCACACACAGCACACACACGCGAACACAGCACACACGAACACAGCACACACAGCACACACACAAACACAGCACACACAUGCACACAGCACACGCACACACAGCACACACAUGAACACAGCACACAGCACACACAUGCACACACAGCACACACGCAUGCACAGCACACAUGAACACAGCACACACACAAACACACAGCACACACAUGCACACACAGCACACACACUCAUGCGCAGCACAUACAUGAACACAGCUCACAGCACACAAACACGCAGCACACACGUUGCACACGCAAGCACCCACCUGCACACACACAUGCGCACACACACGCACACCCCCACAAAAUUGGAUGAAAACAAUAAGCAUAUCUAAGCAACUACGAUAUCUGUAUGGAUCAGGCCAAAGUCCCGCUAAGAUUCUCCAAUGUUUUCAUGGUCUGAGCCCCGCUCCUGUUCCCAUCUCCACUGCCCCUCGGCCCUGUCUGUGCCCUGCCUCUCAGAGGAGGGGGCUCAGAUGGUGCGGCCUGAGUGUGCGGCCGGCGGCAUUUGGGAUACACCCGUAGGGUGGGCGGGGUGUGUCCCAGGCCUAAUUCCAUCUUUCCACCAUGACAGAGAUGCCCUUGUGAGGCUGGCCUCCUUGGCGCCUGUCCCCACGGCCCCCGCAGCGUGAGCCACGAUGCUCCCCAUACCCCACCCAUUCCCGAUACACCUUACUUACUGUGUGUUGGCCCAGCCAGAGUGAGGAAGGAGUUUGGCCACAUUGGAGAUGGCGGUAGCUGAGCAGACAUGCCCCCACGAGUAGCCUGACUCCCUGGUGUGCUCCUGGAAGGAAGAUCUUGGGGACCCCCCCACCGGAGCACACCUAGGGAUCAUCUUUGCCCGUCUCCUGGGGACCCCCCAAGAAAUGUGGAGUCCUCGGGGGCCGUGCACUGAUGCGGGGAGUGUGGGAAGUCUGGCGGUUGGAGGGGUGGGUGGGGGGCAGUGGGGGCUGGGCGGGGGGAGUUCUGGGGUAGGAAGUGGUCCCGGGAGAUUUUGGAUGGAAAAGUCAGGAGGAUUGACAGCAGACUUGCAGAAUUACAUAGAGAAAUUAGGAACCCCCAAAUUUCAUGUCAAUUGAUCUAUUCCCCCUCUUUGUUUCUUGGGGCAUUUUUCCUUUUUUUUUUUUUUUUGUUUUUUUUUUACCCCUCCUUAGCUUUAUGCGCUCAGAAACCAAAUUAAACCCCCCCCCCAUGUAACAGGGGGGCAGUGACAAAAGCAAGAACGCACGAAGCCAGCCUGGAGACCACCACGUCCUGCCCCCCGCCAUUUAUCGCCCUGAUUGGAUUUUGUUUUUCAUCUGUCCCUGUUGCUUGGGUUGAGUUGAGGGUGGAGCCUCCUGGGGGGCACUGGCCACUGAGCCCCCUUGGAGAAGUCAGAGGGGAGUGGAGAAGGCCACUGUCCGGCCUGGCUUCUGGGGACAGUGGCUGGUCCCCAGAAGUCCUGAGGGCGGAGGGGGGGGUUGGGCAGGGUCUCCUCAGGUGUCAGGAGGGUGCUCGGAGGCCACAGGAGGGGGCUCCUGGCUGGCCUGAGGCUGGCCGGAGGGGAAGGGGCUAGCAGGUGUGUAAACAGAGGGUUCCAUCAGGCUGGGGCAGGGUGGCCGCCUUCCGCACACUUGAGGAACCCUCCCCUCUCCCUCGGUGACAUCUUGCCCGCCCCUCAGCACCCUGCCUUGUCUCCAGGAGGUCCGAAGCUCUGUGGGACCUCUUGGGGGCAAGGUGGGGUGAGGCCGGGGAGUAGGGAGGUCAGGCGGGUCUGAGCCCACAGAGCAGGAGAGCUGCCAGGUCUGCCCAUCGACCAGGUUGCUUGGGCCCCGGAGCCCACGGGUCUGGUGAUGCCAUAGCAGCCACCACCGCGGCGCCUAGGGCUGCGGCAGGGACUCGGCCUCUGGGAGGUUUACCUCGCCCCCACUUGUGCCCCCAGCUCAGCCCCCCUGCACGCAGCCCGACUAGCAGUCUAGAGGCCUGAGGCUUCUGGGUCCUGGUGACGGGGCUGGCAUGACCCCGGGGGUCGUCCAUGCCAGUCCGCCUCAGUCGCAGAGGGUCCCUCGGCAAGCGCCCUGUGAGUGGGCCAUUCGGAACAUUGGACAGAAGCCCAAAGAGCCAAAUUGUCACAAUUGUGGAACCCACAUUGGCCUGAGAUCCAAAACGCUUCGAGGCACCCCAAAUUACCUGCCCAUUCGUCAGGACACCCACCCACCCAGUGUUAUAUUCUGCCUCGCCGGAGUGGGUGUUCCCGGGGGCACUUGCCGACCAGCCCCUUGCGUCCCCAGGUUUGCAGCUCUCCCCUGGGCCACUAACCAUCCUGGCCCGGGCUGCCUGUCUGACCUCCGUGCCUAGUCGUGGCUCUCCAUCUUGUCUCCUCCCCGUGUCCCCAAUGUCUUCAGUGGGGGGCCCCCUCUUGGGUCCCCUCCUCUGCCAUCACCUGAAGACCCCCACGCCAAACACUGAAUGUCACCUGUGCCUGCCGCCUCGGUCCACCUUGCGGCCCGUGUUUGACUCAACUCAACUCCUUUAACGCUAAUAUUUCCGGCAAAAUCCCAUGCUUGGGUUUUGUCUUUAACCUUGUAACGCUUGCAAUCCCAAUAAAGCAUUAAAAGUCAUGA